ACUAGCGACGGCCAUGCUGCAUGUGCUGGCCUCGCUGCCUUUGCUGCUCCUGCUGGUGACGUCUGCCUCCACCCACGCCUGGUCGAGACCCCUCUGGUACCAGGUGGGGCUGGACUUGCAGCCCUGGGGGUGUCAGCCAAAGAGUGUGGAGGGCUGUAGGGGUGGCCUGAGCUGUCCUGGCUACUGGCUGGGCCCUGGAGCAAGCCGCAUCUACCCCGUGGCUGCGGUCAUGAUCACCACCACGAUGCUGAUGAUCUGCCGCAAGAUACUGCAGGGGCGGCGGCGCUCACAGGCCACCAAGGGUGAGCAUCCGCAGGUGACCACUGAGCCCUGCGGACCCUGGAAACGGCGGGCCCCAAUCUCAGACCACACCCUGCUCCGUGGGGUCCUGCACAUGCUGGAUGCCCUCCUGGUCCACAUCGAAGGCCACCUACGUCAUCUAGCCACCCAGCGGCAAAUCCAAAUAAAGGGGACUUCCACCCAGAGUGGGUGACCGAACAUGUGCCUCUCUUUGCCUGACAGCCUGAGGUCCUGGGCCAGGUCUGCUCUUUCCAGGCCUGUCUGGACCGUGUGUCC